ACGCUGCCGCCGGCAUCCGCUCGGACGCGGCCACGUUGUCUUGCGCGCUUUGCCCGCCUGGCCCUGGGACUCUGACCCUCGGCUACCCUUUCCUGCCCCACUAGCGUGGCCGCGAGCCUCGGUGAGCCGGCCGUAUUCCCGCUCUCGCUUAGGGGGCACAGGCGCAGGCAUCGGCCCGGCCACUCCAAGCCUUCGGUGCGCGGGCGCGUCUGGGAUACGGGCCCGGGAGGCGCCGCCCUCCGUCCGCCCGGUGCCUCUCAGGAACAGCGAACCGGAGAGAGCGCCGGAGAGUUGGGCUCAGUGCGGAGCUCGGCGCCGGGGCCCAUGCCCGUGCGCCCCCGCAGGCCGGCGCCAUGGCCUCCGGGAGUGUGGCCGAGUGCCUGCAGCAGGAGACCACCUGCCCCGUGUGCCUGCAGUACUUCGCAGAGCCCAUGAUGCUCGACUGCGGCCAUAACAUCUGUUGCGCGUGCCUCGCCCGCUGCUGGGGCACGGCAGAGACUAACGUGUCGUGCCCGCAGUGCCGGGAGACCUUCCCGCAGAGGCACAUGCGGCCCAACCGGCACCUGGCCAACGUGACCCAACUGGUAAAGCAGCUGCGCACCGAGCGGCCGUCGGGGCCCGGCGGCGAGAUGGGCGUGUGCGAGAAGCACCGCGAGCCCCUGAAGCUGUACUGCGAGGAGGACCAGAUGCCCAUCUGCGUGGUGUGCGACCGCUCCCGCGAGCACCGCGGCCACAGCGUGCUGCCGCUCGAGGAGGCGGUGGAGGGCUUCAAGGAGCAAAUCCAGAACCAGCUCGACCAUUUAAAAAGAGUGAAAGAUUUAAAGAAGAGACGUCGGGCCCAGGGGGAACAGGCACGAGCUGAACUCUUGAGCCUAACCCAGAUGGAGAGGGAGAAGAUUGUUUGGGAGUUUGAGCAGCUGUAUCACUCCUUAAAGGAGCAUGAGUAUCGCCUCCUGGCCCGCCUUGAGGAGCUAGACUUGGCCAUCUACAAUAGCAUCAAUGGUGCCAUCACCCAGUUCUCUUGCAACAUCUCCCACCUCAGCAGCCUGAUCGCUCAGCUAGAAGAGAAGCAGCAGCAGCCCACCAGGGAGCUCCUGCAGUGGCUCACACCUCAGACAAAUGGGGAGAAACUCCAAGAAUUAAGAGAGGCUCAGUUAUACUCAGUGGACGUGACUCUGGACCCAGACACGGCCUACCCCAGCCUGAUCCUCUCUGAUAAUCUGCGGCAAGUGCGGUACAGUUACCUCCAACAGGACCUGCCUGACAACCCCGAGAGGUUCAAUCUGUUUCCCUGUGUCUUGGGCUCUCCAUGCUUCAUCGCCGGGAGACAUUAUUGGGAGGUAGAGGUGGGAGAUAAAGCCAAGUGGACCAUAGGUGUCUGUGAAGACUCAGUGUGCAGAAAAGGUGGAGUAACCUCAGCCCCCCAGAAUGGAUUCUGGGCAGUGUCUUUGUGGUAUGGGAAAGAAUAUUGGGCUCUUACCUCCCCAAUGACUGCCCUACCCCUGCGGACCCCGCUCCAGCGGGUGGGGAUUUUCUUGGACUAUGAUGCUGGUGAGGUCUCCUUCUACAACGUGACAGAGAGGUGUCACACCUUCACUUUCUCUCAUGCUACCUUUUGUGGGCCUGUCCGGCCCUACUUCAGUCUGAGUUACUCGGGAGGGAAAAGUGCAGCUCCUCUGAUCAUCUGCCCCAUGAGUGGGAUAGAUGGGUUUUCUGGCCAUGUUGGGAAUCAUGGUCAUUCCAUGGAGACCUCCCCUUGAGGAGGUGAAUUCAGGCCAAAAGGGCUGUUGGCUGUAAUCCUACGCCAGGCACAAGGCAUCUUGUUGCCUUGCCACGUCCUGUCACAGCUGGGUAUCCUUACCAUGUUCCACGCCCUUGCAGUGGGAGACAGGAUGUCCAUGUUCUCUACCAUCCUUUUCCUUCCCAUGCAGAUUGUGAAAUGUAAUGAGAUGUAUCAAGAUAUCCUAGAAAUAAAAACCAGAUGUCCACCUCCAGUGUUUCAUACUUUCUGGUUUUACACAUCGCUGGAGGGAUAAAGAGUAUGGAUAAUCUUUGGAUUUGGAGAGCCGUUCAAGAUACUUCCAGCUUCUUGGCUCAGCCUGGCUUCCUCUGGUUCAGCCCCACAUAAUGAUUAUGGCUAUUUGCUGUCAUUUCUGGGCUAGGGCUCCUUUCUAACAACCUAGACUGGAAUAAGGCCCUGUCAGCAUGGCUCCCUUUAUCCCAGUUUUCCGUCUGGGAACAGUACCUCUGCCCCUGAUUCCCAAUGUGCCAUAGUUUUAUUAACUCCAUUAAAGAAGCCUGUAUGUGUUUUGGUUAGUUACAGUUAUUUUACAAUAAUGGUGGGUAAUGGCCCCACCUCUGUUAUGAGAUAAUGUUCUAAUCAAUGUCUCUGCCUUUGUAUCUUUUCUGAGGGCUUUGUCUGUUCUCUUCAUUCUAAUGAAAGGUGUAUUCUAGUGCUGGGUGCAUAUCAUCCAGGAUAAUAUUCUGCCCAACUCCAUCCUCUGUUACUAGAUCCCUUACCAGUCACAUUUGUGGACUGGUGGCCAGUCGUAUACCAUCCCUGGAAGGAUUCUGGGACAAUAUUCCAGGGAUUCAUUGACUUCUUGGCUCCUUUUCUCCAUUUCCUUUGGGGGAAGGGGGAAUUGACCAUGCUUAAGUGCAUCCUAUCAAGGGGCAGCUCCGUCCCCAUGGCCAUUGGAUCAUGAGACACUCUGAAGUCAGAAGGCUGGGGCAGAUCACUUCAAGCAAGCCCCCAUGAUGGUUCUCAGUCCUGCUUCUCUGUGGGUACGUGCCCCUCUGUUUAAAAAUAAACUGAAUAUGGAUGUUUA